GGUUCGGAGCCUCGUCUCAAUCACUCUCGCUGUAACCGGCCGUCACGCUGAUCCGCUCCAGCCUCCAGCCACACGCUGCGCGCUUGGCGAACUAGGGAUGAGGGAGAGUUUUUUGCCUGGGGGCCAAAGCCCCCGGGAGCUCUCGGAGCAGCAGCCCUACUCGGGAUGUGCCUGUGGGCCUCCCGCUGCAGGCUGGGCGCUAUCCACCUGCUGGGGGCCCUGAGGCAGGGGAGGCGUCACGCGUGGCCCGACCUGGCCCUGCCUCUCCCUUCCCCGCUGGGCCCGCGUCCCAUCCCGUCUCCUUCCGCCUCCGCCAGCGCCGAGGAAUGUGGCGAGGCCGGCUGGGCGGCUCGAACGCCUGGGUCCCCCUCCGCUCCCAGUUCGCAAGUGCGGAGGCCAGAUGCGAGAGCUCCCGCUGCGGAGACCUGGACGAGGGGGAGAAGUCAUCCCAGGAUUGGGGGAGGCAGUGUGGAAGAAGGGAAAAUGAGGAGGAGAGGGUGCCUUGGAGCCUGGCAGAACGAGCUCACCUCUCCUGUUUCAAAGAUGGGGAAACUAAGGCCCGGAGACGGGAAGAGACUUGCCCAAGGUUCCACAGGUCCCCUGGAAGUGACGCUGACUCAGCCAGUGAGGAGCGGGCCUGUCUCCAACAGGCUGCAGAGCUGGGAGGAGACUUGGAGCCUCAUCCCGGAGAAAGGGCUGCCGGAGGACGACCCGGACAUCGUUGUGAAAGGUUGGCUGUACCGGGAGCCCCGCGGAGGAGGGGCGCGGCCCUGGCUGCCCCCGCGCCGAGCCUGGUUUGUGCUCACGCGGGACUCCCUGGAUCAGUUCAGCAGCAGCGGGAAAGGGGCGCGGCGUCUCGGGAGCCUCGUGCUCACCAGCCUGUGCUCGGUGACCGGCCCAGAGCGCAGGCGUAAGGAGACAGGUCUGUGGUCAGUGACUGUGUCUGGUCGGAAACACAGUGUCCGCCUCUGCUCCCCACGCCAGGCAGAGGCUGAGCGCUGGGGGGUGGCAUUGCGGGAAGUGAUCGCCUCCAAGGCACCCCUGGAGACCCCCACCCAGCUACUGCUCAGGGACAUACAGGAAAGUUGCGGGGACCCAGAGGCCGUUGCCCUCAUUUACCUGAGGAACCCGAUUCUGAGACACACUAGUGGAGCCUUGUAUGCCCCACUCCUGCCCCUGCCCUAUGGAGUCAGCGCCCCAGGUCCGGGCUAUGCACCCCUGCGCGAGGAGGCGGUGCGGCUGUUCUUGGCGCUGCAGGCGCUGGAGGGGGCGCGGCGCCCCGGGCCCUUGAUGCAGGGUGUGCUCCAAACCUGCCGGGACUUGCCCGCGCUCCGGGAUGAACUCUUCCUGCAGCUGGCUAAGCAGACCUCGGGCCCUGCAGGUCCCCCCGGGCUCCCGGCUACCCAAGACCCUGCGGCCCUGCGGUACUGGCAACUCCUCACCUGCAUGAGCUGCACCUUCCGACCUGGGGGAGCUGUGCGGGGGCACCUCCUGGGGCACUUGGAGAGGACCGAGCAGGCACUCCCGGACUCGGAACUGGCGGAAUAUGCGCGCUUCAUCCGGAAAGCGCUGGGCCGGACGCGCGGCAGAGAGCUGGUGCCCUCGCUGGCGGAGAUUUCCGCGUUGAGCCAACGGCAGGAGCUGCUGUGUACCGUGCACUGUCCGGGGGCUGGUGCCUGUGCUGUGGCCAUCGACUCCCACACCACGGCGGGGGAGGUGGCUCGAGAGCUGGUGGGGCGGCUGGGCUUGGCCCGGAGCCGCAACGCAUUCGCGCUGUACGAGCAGCGAGGGGCCCAGGAGCGAGCCCUGGCUGGGGGGACCCUCGUGGCCGACGUGCUCACCAGGUUUGAGAACUUGGCCGCGGAGGAAGCUGGGUUGGAGGACUCGCCCGACUCCGGGUGGAGACUAUGUCUGCGUCUUCACGGACCUCUGCACCCUGAGGGGCUGUCCCCAGACGGUCACGAACUGCCUUUCCUCUUUGAGCAGGCUCACGCUCUGCUGCUGCGGGGCCGGCCGCCCCCACCCGACGACACGCUGCGCGCCCUGGCGGCGCUGCGCCUGCAGAGCCUGCAGCGGGACUUCUCUCCGCGGGUGCCCCUGCCCCGCCUGGACCGCCUGCUCCCGCCCCCGGCCCCGCCGCGCGAAGACCCGCCCCGCCCGACCCCCAGGCCGCCCCCUUCCGCUGCCCUGCUGGCCGGGGCGCUCUGGAGCCCGGGCCUGGCCAAGAGGCGGGCGGAGCGGGCCCGGCGCGGCGGGGCCGGCCGCACUGCGGGAAGCAUUGCCCGCGAGGGAGGAGGCGGCGCCGGCACGGCAGCUGCCGUGCUGGGCGGCUGGAAGCGGCUACGGGGCAUGGGCCGAGCUGAGGCCAUGGCCGCCUACCUGGCCCUGGCGGCGCAGUGUCCGGGGUUCGGCGCUGCUCGGAGCCUGGUCGGGGUGCUCCACAGAAGCUGUGCCUGGGCUUGGGAGCCAAGGCCAUGUCCCUCUCCCGGCCAGGGGAGACGGAGCCCAUCCACAGUGUCAGCUAUGGCCAUGUGGCCGCCUGCCAGCUAAUGGGCCCCCACACCCUGGCCUUGAGGGUGGGAGAGAGCCAGCUCCUCCUGCAGAGCCCCCAGGUGAGUGAGAAGAGGAGUUGUGGGAGGAGGAGAGAAGGGAAGCGAUGUCAGGAAGCAUUUACAGAACACCAAACCUGGGCCAGGUAGAGCUCUAAGCACUGGGGAUCCAGCAGUGAUCACAGACAAGCUGAAGGAGCUUACACUAGAGUGGAGUCAGACAAUAAACAAGGAAUCCCAGGCUAUGAAGACAGUGAGAAAUGCUACAAAGGAAAGAGUGAUGUGACAGGAAGCCAGGGAAGGGUUCUCAAAAAGGGUGCCAUUUAAGCUAGCCAGGGAAGACCUGGGAGAACAGCAUUCCAGGUAGAAAGAAUUGCAAGGUGGCCGGGUGCAGUGGCUCAUGCCUGUAAUCCCAGCACUUUGGGAGGCCGAGGCGGGCAGAUCACGAGGUCAGGAGAUCGAGACCAUCCUGACCAACAUGGCGAAACCCCAUCUCUACUAAAAAUACAAAUUAGCUGGGGCUGGUGGCGCACACCUAUAGUCCCAGCUACUCGGGAAGCUGAGGUAGGAGAAUUGCUUGAACCCGGCAGGCGGAGGUUGCAGUGAGCCGAGGCACUUCAGCCUGGCAACAGAGCAAGACUCCGUCUCAACAACAACAACAACAACAACAACAAAAAAAAAUGUUAGAAGAGCAGAAAGAACCAAGUAUAACUGGCACAUAGAAAUGAAGGAGAGAAGCCGGCCGCGGUGGCUCACGCCUGUAAUCCCAGCACUUUGGGAGGCCGAGAUGGGCGGAUCAUGAGGUCAGGAGAUCGAGACCAUCUUGGCUAACACGGUGAAACCCUGUUUCUACUAAAAAUACAAAAAAUUAGCCGGGCGUGUUGGCGGGCGCCUGUAGUCCCAGCUACUCAGGAGGCUGAGGCAGGAGAAUGGUGUGAACCCAGGAGGCGGAGCUUGCAGUGAGCUGAGAUCGCGCCACUGCACUCCAACCUGGGGGACACAGCGAGACUCCGUCUCAAAAAACAAAAAAGAAAUGAAGGAGAGAGUGGUGAUAAGGAAGGAAAGGUUGCAGGGCCAGAGCACGUAGGACCCUGGUGGGGAAGCUGGAGCCCUAGAGCCUGGAGAAAGGAUGAGAAAAAGAAGAGAACCUGGCAGCCCCUGUUGCACACUGACCUCUGCCCUCUCUUAGGUGGAAGAGAUCAUGCAGCUGGUGAAUGCCUACUUGGCCAACCCCUCCCCCGAGAGGCCCUGCAGCAGCUCUUCUCCUCCAUGCCAAGACCUGCCAGACACCUCCCCUCCCAGCCAGCGCCCGGGCCUGGACGAGCCCCAGGGACAGUCUGGCUGCUUGGGGCAGCUGCAGGACUGAGCCUGCCAAGAGGUCACGACUUCCCUCCUGCCUGCAGCCUGGGCCAGGACUGCUCUGAGAUUUGAGGGAAACAUGGACCCUUUUGGCCCUGCAGGGACAGGGCACAUCCCACACCCAAGGGCUACAAUGGGUGUGGGUAAUUUUCUAGUUUGUUUCUUAAUUUAUUUGUAGAAGAGAAGCAAAAAAAAAAAAAAAGUUUCUUAUUUACACAAA